UCCCACAACACGUGGGGAUUAUGGGAACUACAAUUCAAGGUGAGAUUUGGGUGGGGACACAGACAAACCGUAUCACAUCCUAAACCCUUUGCAUGAGUGAAAUUGAAUGUUGGCACACAACGUUUCACCUUUUGGGAGCUAGCCUUUUCUUGCUAGGGUAAAAGAAUUCAGGUAUUAAUAAAACUAAUGUGAUUAUAUGGAAAGAUUAUACAGUAUGGAAGGAACAUUUUAAGAACAUGAGGUUAGAGAUUGUGCCAUGUUUCUCUUGUGGACAAGAACAUAGGGGCCCAUAAAUGGAGAUUCCUUGUUUUCCUUUAACCUUCAUCUAAUGUGUCUUAGGUAUUACAUCUCAGGAUGUAAAUGAUAAGAGGCCAUAUUUAUGAAAGGACUAAUAUUUUUGUACUUAUCUUAGUGUCUGAAGGAUGUAGGCCUGGUAGUUCCUCAUACGGAGUAGGGUGAGGCCCUAGUCACUGUCUACUGUUAACCAAAAGAGGUGGGCAGGAACCCCUGGCCUACACACCUUUGCCAUUGUAGGAAAUAUAGCAUAGGCAUUACAUCUAAAGCAAGCUUUCCUAAUAUUACUACCCUGUUCCUAACUACCAAUGGUUCUUUUUUUUUUUUUUUUUUUUUUGAGAUGGAGUCUCACUGUUGCCCAGGCUGGAGUGCAGUGGCGCGAUCCCGACUCACUGCAGGCUCUGCCCCACGGGGUUCACGCCAUUCUCCAGCCUCAGCCUCCUGAGUAGCUGGGACUACAGGCGCCAAUGGUUCUUUAUUUAUGAAAAGCCCCUUGUAAAACCUGGUUCAAGUAAAACAUUUUGUGAUUUAUUUAAUUGUUGCAUAUGAAUAAAUAUAGUUUUUAAAAAGUAUCAGAUGAAAAUGUAUAUCUAUGAACUUACCACUAUACUUAGAAGUAAAGUUAUCAACAUCUUUCACUCCUCUACAUAUUUCUCCUUUAACCCAUUUUUCUGGUCCUUCUUAAAAGUAAUCACUCUUAAAUUUUGUGCUUAUUCUGUUGUUUUAAAAAAUAGUUUAAACAAAUAUGUGUGUACUCCUAAACAUAGGUUACUUUUGCUUCUUUUUGAGAUAUAUUUAAAUUUUAUUGUGGUCUACAUAUUCUUCAGCAGUUUGUUUUUUUACCCAAUAUUAUGUUUCAUCUGUAUUACUGCAUUUACUAUCCCUAGUUGAUUCACUUCCCUGAAGUACAAUAUUCAGUUGUGUGGCUAUACCAUAAUUUAGUUAUUCAUUUUGUUGUCAGUAAAAUUUGGGUGAUUAUCAGAUUUUUUUCUAGCAUGAAAAAUGCUACUAGGAACAUUCGUGUAUGUGUCUAAUGGUAUACACUUUCAAGUGUUUUUUUAUAUAUGUGAGAGUAGAUUACUUGGACCUUGAAGAUGAACAUGCUAUCUUUUCCAGAUACUGCCAAUUAUUUCAGCAAGAUAUGAGUUCCCAUCAUUUUAUAUUUGUCAGCAUUUGAUAUUUCCAGGCCUAGUGAUUUCCAGUCAUUUACUGGAUAUAAUAUGAUUAUCUCUGUAGGGAGUUGAUUUCCAUCUCCUCAAUUACUAAUAAAGUUAAAAAUCUUUUCAUAUGUUUUAUUGCCAUUUUUAUUUCUUCUGUAAAGUACCUACUCAUGGCUUUUUCUCAUUUUUUGUUUGUCAUCAUUGAAUUAUAGGAGUUUUGAGAGAGUGAGCAAGCUAGUCUGUGUGUGUGUGUGUGUGCGUGUGUGUGUAUCUCCUUAAUGUGUUAUAUGUGAUUGGAACUUCUUCUCCCACUUUGAUGCUUCCUUUCUUCCCCACUUGUUUUAGGUAUCUUCUGAUGAAGUGGAGUUAUUUAUGGUAUGUUCUCAGGAGCUACAAUUUUUAAUUUCAAUGUAAUCAGUGUUUUUAAUUAUCUUAUGUUUAGCUCUUUUGGGUCAUGCUUAGGAAAUUCUUCUUAAAUUUCAUUGAUAACAGUCUUCCAUACUUUCUUCUAAAGUCUUAUAUUUUGGCCUUUCAUAUUUAUUCCUUUAAUCCACCUGGAGUAGAUUUUUUUUUUCCCUCUGUAGAGUUUGGAGUAGAGAUUUUAUUUCCUUUUUUUUUUUUUUUUUUUUUCUUUUUUUUUGAGACAGAGUCUUGCUCUGUCGCCCAGGCUGGAGUGCAGUGGCACUAUCUCAGCUCACUGCAACCUCCACCUCCUGGGUUCAAGCGAUUCUCCUGCCUCCGCCUCCCGAGUAGCUGGGACUACAGGCAUGUGCCACCACGCCCAGCUAAUUUUUUGUAUUUUUUUUAGUAGAGAUGGGGUUCCACCAUGUUAGCUAGGAUGAUUUCGAUUUCCUGACCUUGUGAUCCGCCCGCCUCGGCCUCCCAAAAUGCUGGGAUUAUAGGUGUGAGCCACCACGUGGCCUCAUUUCAUUCUUUCAUGUGGAUAGGCAGUUGUUCCAGAAGUAUAUAGUGAGGAGCUUCUUCUUUCUCUAAUGAUCUGCAAUGUCACCUUCAUCAUUUAUGAAGGUUGCACAUAUACAUGGGAAUUUUUUAGUCUGGCAUUAAAUGUUCUUCAAAAGAGUUCCUGCAAACGUUUUUGUUUUUAUUUCCUACUGUUCCCUUCACGUACUCUCUACUGAACUAAACUCUGUAAUGUGUCUCGAAACUGUCCCACAAUUUUCCUUGUCUUAAGAGUUUAAUGCUUUCAUACACCUCUCACAUUCAGCCUUGUGCUAUUGUCUUAGGUAUAUUUAUUUCUCUUUUGCUCCCAAUUAUGUUGUAAACUUUUGGAAGCAGGAAGGAUAUAUUGUUCAUCUUUGGUAGCAUUAAACAAUGAAUACAGUGUUUUUUACUUAAUAGAUAUUUGGUAAAUCAUUGAACUAAAUUGGGGUUUGGAAUUGAAGGUCUUAGAAAUUACCUGACCACUCCCAUUAUAUUUGCCCAUCCAUGAUCACUGAGAUUUAUAGAGAUUAGAUGCAAUGCCCAGUUUCACAUAUGUUUUUGCAUCACUGUCUCUUUUUUUCUUGAGCUUAUUCCAGAGUGUCUUUUAAUAUCCAUUCCAUGAUCAAAUGGCUGAACUAUUAAAAUGCUGUCCAGAAGUGUAAAGCAAUAUGAAGAUGCUAGAAAAGUUGAAGAGACACAUAUAUGGUAGGUCCAAGACCAUUACACUUACUGAGUCCAUUACUAAAAAUGAUGUUCACUUAACAUCAAAACACUCAGGAUUACCCAAGCACAAUAUACUGAUUUGCACCUCUGCCUUUGUUCAUGCCCCUUGUUCAGGAGAACUGCUUUCAUGUGCUACUGUCCAUAGAUCUUCUCUAUCCUUACAGAUUAAUUUCUUCCUUUUGAAUGCUAUGUUUCCAUACUUUGACAUUCCUUCUGCACCAUUCAGACCAUAUUUUAGUUCUUUUUUAUGGUAUCUCUCACUUUUGAUUGUCACCCCUUAAGUCAAAGACAAUUUUUUCAUCUGUGUCUUCUCAACACCCAGCACAGGGCUAUGUUUGGUAAAAAUUAGGUAUCCAAGAUGUACUAAAUGAAAAAAUCAAAGAAGCAAAAAUUUUUGAAAUUUCAAAUGAGCUUAUAAAUAAGCUCUGUUAUGUACUUAUUGUAAGAAGUUUGAAAAUAGAGAAAAGUAUUAAAGAGAACAGAAAUCUCUAAAAAAUCCCAAAAUAACCACCUCAGGGGAGUUCUUAAGUUAGAAGCCACAUCUCUCAUGGUACCCCUGUUGAUCUGCAGGUCUCUGCUGGUUUCUCUUAGUCGCCACCAUUUUGGAAGAGGAACAUCCAGUCACUCAAGUGCUAAACUAACACUCUAGCGUUGCUCUUCUUAUCAUCUCAGAAUGUUUGCUUCCUGGUAACUGGUGCUAAGUAUCUUGUAUGUUCUGUUACACAUCUUCAAUGCUUUGGAUAAUGUCAAAAUACCACAUAGUUGUUAUUUUUAACAACUGGUCAUCCUGAGUAGACGCACCCAUCCAUCAUAGUGACUCAAGGCCACCAGUAGCAAGCUCUUCAGAAAAGUUAUGGAGUAGUACUUUGUGUUAAAUGAGCUAAUUAAGAGACACAAACCAACAUCAUUUUUUUUUAAUCUCUCAGGAUGAGGAUGUUGUGUGGAUAGAUUACUAUUCUGAUAUUUAGAACAGAGGUUUGUUUGUUUAAAAAUUGUAUUUAUUUAAUCUCCCAAAACAACUGAGAAGGCUGGUUUUUCUACUCCUGGUAUGCUACCAUAUACUAGAUUUGUCUCAGCAUCAGAUCUUGGCUAAUAUGAGCUCUUCUGACAACUGUAGACACAGAGAAAUUGGGGUGUGUUUAGUUAGAAUAUUUACUGUUCUUAUGUGUGUUGAGAAUAUCUCAGUUGUGGUAUAGCCUCACCUCUAAGCAAUGACAUCAUGACAUAUAUUCAAAUUAUAUUCUGCUUUUUUUGUCUUAGAUAGAAAUAAACAAUUACAUGGAAUUUUCAUAGGCAAAUUAAUUAAGAUGAGAGCAAUCAGUCUUUGCCUAGUCUCCUUCCCACCUUCUUCUCAAAGUGAUUUAUUAAUAAACUGCAUCUGAAAUAAUUAAGAGGUAGAAAAUAAAAAUCUGAAGACCAUAUUUCAUAGCAGACUUCAAUUUUAUAUGAAGGUCUCAAUUUAUUCAUUCCUCCAUCACCACCAUCUUUCAUAGCCAAAGUACUCAUCUCUAAAUGGAAGGUUUCUAAAAUUCCUCAUCUAUAGAAGUGCCUUCCCCUAUGUGUAUACACACAUACAUGGUGUUAGUGUUUUGUAGCUAAUGGUUCCCUAUGUAGCACGUUGAAUGUGUGUUUAUAUUUCUUCAUAAAGCACCUCGAUGGCAGGGACUUGUUAUUUUCUAAAUCUUUGUAUACUUGUUUGGGACAUUUUAGUCACUGAAGGAAUAAUAGAUGAGUGGAUGAAUAGGUACCAACUACAAUGAAUAUUUGUGGGUUAAUUGAGCUCUGACUGCAUAACUUUUUUUAAUAUACUUUAAAUUCAGGGGUACCUGUGCAGAACAUGCAGGUUUUUACAUAGGUAUACAUGUGUCAUGGUGGUUUGCUGCACCCAUUAACCCGUCAUCUACAUUAGGUAUUUCUCCUAAUGCUAUCCCUCCCAUAGCCCCGAACGCCCUGACGGGAGUUUUAUGUGAUAAUAUGAGUGUCUGCUAUGGGCCAUUCAUUGUGCUAGAUGCUUACCAUAAAAAUGUCUUCAUUUGUACAAUAACCUUAUAAAAUGAACAUUAUUAUGUGCUUUACAAAAAAAAAAAGAAACUAAAACUCAGGUAUAUACUUUCCUAAGUCCAUACUUCCAAGAAGUGGAGCAGGAAGAAUUUGAACACAGGGCAGCCUAACUCCAACACAUAUGUGCUGUCCUGGUAUCAUAUCAAGGUGCUUCUAACUUCAUAAUGAAGAGGAUGGACAUAGAAUUGUCCAGGAUUCUUUGGAUAUAUUGGAUAUAAUAUGCCUUUUAGACCCAGCUGUAGUUUGUUUUCCAAAGUAGCUAUUCCCAGCUUCUCCUUAGCCACUAGAUACGGUAGGGAGUUCCCUGAGCAAAUACAUACUGAAAUCCAUCUUUUUGGUUUUGUUUUUGGCUCUCCUGCUCUUUUUUUGUUUUUUUUUUUUUUUUGUUUUUUGUUUUUUUUUGACUGAGUCUCACUCUGUUGCCAAGCUGGAGUACUGCGGCAACGUCUCGGCUCACUGCAACCUCUGAUUCCCUGGUUCAAGCAAUUGUCUUGCCUUAGCCUCCUGAGUAGCUGGGAUUACAGGCACGCACCACCACGCCCAGCUAAUUUUUUUAUUUGUAGUAGAGACGGGGUUUCACCAUGUUGGUCAGGUGAUCACGAUCUCCUGACCUCGUGAUCCACCUGCCUCGGCCUCCCAAAGUGUUGAGAUUACAGGCGUCAGCCAACGCGCCCAGCCUGGCUAUCUCUUAUAUUACCUGUUUAUAGAUCACAGUUUUUCCUACUGUGUAACUGUCCUUGGGCACAGAUUCUGUUUCCCCAUUCGGUGCCUAAAUAGCACAGAAAUGAUAGAGUCUGGCUCUCUGGGGCACUGGUCUGCCAGCAGGCACCCUACUAGUGUUAUGCUGGCUGAUGACUGGACUCUAACUCUCACAGUGCUUGCUGUUUCAGGGCCUGAUGCUUUCUGUACAUCCAGAGGACUAGGUUUAAAAUUGCAAUAGUAAUACCUUUUCCAUGGAGUCAGUGUUAUGUAUGACAUGACCUUGCUUUGGGCAAAGAUUAUGCAUGCAUUGAUAUACAAACGAAUAAUAGUUGGUGGUAUGAAUUAUACGCCAAAUUGUCGCCUCAGGUAAAAUCAGUAACCUGCAUUUCUAACUGAGCUUUUAUUGCCAGAGACUCCCUAAGACUAUUGACACCAUUGGUCAGUAUUACCGCAGGAGAAUUCAUACGUAUUUAACACACCCAUGCACCUUGCUAGCCAGAUUGCAGAUCCUAUUUUAUUAAGUUCUCAAAGGGAGAAAAGUGACAUUGCAGAGAGGAAAAUAAAAGUAAAAGUGAUUAAGUAGCUUUCCUGAGUCAUAACAAAUUGUGAGCAAUGGAUCUAAAUUUAUUCAUUUUCAAUUCAUUCCAAAACAAUGUAUGGAGUACAUUUAUUGUAUACACAUGUGUCUUAAUCCAUUCGUGGUACUAUAACAAAAUGCCUUAGACUUGGUAGUUUAUACAUAGUAGACAUUUCUUGCUCAUGGUUUUGGAGGUUGGCAAGUCCAAGAUAUCAAUGUGCCUGAGAUUUGAUGUCUAGGAGGGCUGCUCUCUGCUUCCAAGAUGAUGCUUUCUUGCUGCAUCGUCACAUGGAGGAAGGGAGGAACAGUGUUCUUACAUGGUGGAAGGGCAAAAAAAGGGACACACUUGCUGCCUCAACCCAUUUUAUAAGGGGGCAAAUCCUGUUUCAUCAGGGCAGAGCCCUCAUGGCCUAAUUACCUCCCAAAGUCUCCACCUCUUCAUAUGGUUGCAUUGGGGAUUAAAUUUCAACAUGAUUUUUAGAGAGACACAAACAUUCAAACCAUAGUAAUAUGUUAUUUUUAAAAGAGACAGUAGAGAAUAGUGGCAGAGCACACAGUGUGGGGGAUCAGACUACUUGAGUUAGGAUUCACUUUUUAGUACUUAUGAGCUGUGUGUCCUUAGGAAAAUAAUUGAACCUUUCUGUGUUUCCGUCUCCUCAUCUGUAAAAUGGGGAUAAAUAAUAGUACCUACCACAUCAGGGUGUUGUGAGGAUUAAGCAAAUUAAUAUAUGCAAAGUAUUUAAAAUAUUUAUAAUAGAUAAUAUUUUAUCUACAUUUAUUAUUAAUACUACUGCUGCUGCUGUAUUUGAGACACUGUGCUGGAAACUGAGAUCUAGAAAUAAAAGCGACUAUAGCUGCCAUCAAAGAUCUUUCAGUUUAGCAAGGGAGAUGCCAGAAUAAACUCUAUAAGGAAAAGUGGGAAAUGCAGGGAGUGAAACAUCUCAGAGUGCUAUGGCAUCACAGCCAAGAGCCUCCCGAAUCUUUGAAGUAGGAGUUUACCCAGAGGAAGUGAUCACUGAUCUGUGUGGUGAAUUUUGAGUGGGAAUCAUGCAGAGAAGGUUUGAGAGACAGGUGAUUCAGGGCAGCACCAAGAAGACCAAAGCCCGUUAUCUGGAGAAGUACUCUUCCCCCUGGCUGUUUAGGUCUGUCUGGGAAGGUGCAUUCAACAGAAAACAAAACCUUAUAUUCCAUGGAAAAAGGAAAAAGAUAAAUGUCCUUGGGAGCAGUUAAGUGUUGGUUUGUUCUGUGGUGUUGAGCUCUAAACUCCAGUCCUUUCGAUAAUGUAAUUCCUAACAGUGGGGUGGAGAAGGCAGAGAGAAGAAAAGCCAGUGUAUUAAAGAAAAGGCUGUGGAUUUCUGAAAGGAAUGAGAAUUCACACACCAAGGAAGAAUCUUCAGAGAAGGGAGAGGAGGUGGUUGGCAGUGGCUGGCUGGUAGUUAGGAUGGAAGGGGAUUGGGGAGUGGACACAGAUUUUACCCACAUUGCAGUACUUUCCUGGGCAGAAGUGAAUGCUGGCUGGACGUGAGCUACCAUAAUAGUUGUUUGGAAAAGAAUUGGUUCCAUCAGAAGUAGACGCCAUGCAGAUUUGAGCUGAGGCUGCUGCCUCGUGUUUUAUUUUCCAGCCGUGGACUCCAGGGUGCUAUAUAUUAUUACUCUAGAUGCAGUAACUACUCCCCAUCACGUUGGUAGUUCAUUUUUACCUUUUCCAAGUGAACACUUUAGUCAGACUGAUUUACGUUUUUUCCUCCUCUCUGAAAUAGAGGAGUGCUCUUUAGCACUUUUACCCUUUGAAAAUAUAAAAUCACUCAAGGGCUUUCAUAUUUUCAAAGGGCAGAAGCAACUUUAGCGAGAGAGAAGAGUGCAAAAAGCUGACUGAUCUUUUUUUUUUUUUUUAAAUGCUGUAAUGAAAACAUGUAGAAGACAUAUCCUGCGGGCCAGUGUAUGUGGACGCUGGUAAAAAGGUGGAGGAAGUGGGGAGGGGUGAGAGGGCAGGGAAGGGUACACAUUUGGAAAGUGAAACUGUUCCGCUGUAGCUGGAAUUUGAUUUUUAUUUUUUCCUUUUAAAGUCACUGGAGGAGAAAUAGUCCUUAUCAUUUUUCCCCCCAGGUUCAUGCUAGGAUACAAAUAAAAAAGUGUCUCUGAAGAUUUUAAUUGAGAAAACGACUGCCUCCUUCUUUGGCAAUGAUUUGCCAAAUCUCUAACCGCUGAGAAUGAAAUCAACGCACCAUCAGGAACUUGCCAGUGUUAUUCCUGAGUGAAUUUUGCCUUCAGAGUGACAGGUAUAGUUAUGUCUUCUCGAAAGUGCAGAGGGAACGGUUCACCUGUCAGGAACUGACAAUGGCGAAGCCCUUCCCGAAUCCAUCCCAUCAGCUCCUGGGACACUGCCUCAUUUCAUAGAGGAGCCAGAUGAUGCUUAUAUUAUCAAGAGCAACCCUAUUGCACUCAGGUGCAAAGCGAGGCCAGCCAUGCAGAUAUUCUUCAAAUGCAACGGCGAGUGGGUCCAUCAGAACGAGCACGUCUCUGAAGAGACUCUGGACGAGAGCUCAGGUUUGAAGGUCCGCGAAGUGUUCAUCAAUGUUACUAGGCAACAGGUGGAGGACUUCCAUGGGCCCGAGGACUAUUGGUGCCAGUGUGUGGCGUGGAGCCACCUGGGUACCUCCAAGAGCAGGAAGGCCUCUGUGCGCAUAGCCUAUUUACGGAAAAACUUUGAACAAGACCCACAAGGAAGGGAAGUUCCCAUUGAAGGCAUGAUUGUACUGCACUGCCGCCCACCAGAGGGAGUCCCUGCUGCCGAGGUGGAAUGGCUGAAAAAUGAAGAGCCCAUUGACUCUGAACAAGACGAGAACAUUGACACCAGGGCUGACCAUAACCUGAUCAUCAGGCAGGCACGGCUCUCGGACUCAGGAAAUUACACCUGCAUGGCAGCCAACAUCGUGGCUAAGAGGAGAAGCCUGUCGGCCACUGUUGUGGUCUACGUGAAUGGAGGCUGGUCUUCCUGGACAGAGUGGUCAGCCUGCAAUGUUCGCUGUGGUAGAGGAUGGCAGAAACGUUCCCGGACCUGCACCAACCCAGCUCCUCUCAAUGGUGGGGCCUUUUGUGAGGGAAUGUCAGUGCAGAAAAUAACCUGCACUUCUCUUUGUCCUGUGGAUGGGAGCUGGGAAGUGUGGAGCGAAUGGUCCGUCUGCAGUCCAGAGUGUGAACAUUUGCGGAUCCGGGAGUGCACAGCACCACCCCCGAGAAAUGGGGGCAAAUUCUGUGAAGGUCUAAGCCAGGAAUCUGAAAACUGCACAGAUGGUCUUUGCAUCCUAGAUAAAAAACCUCUUCAUGAAAUAAAACCCCAAAGCAUUGAGAAUGCCAGCGACAUUGCUUUGUACUCGGGCUUGGGUGCUGCCGUCGUGGCCGUUGCAGUCCUGGUCAUUGGUGUCACCCUUUACAGACGGAGCCAGAGUGACUAUGGCGUGGACGUCAUUGACUCUUCUGCAUUGACAGGUGGCUUCCAGACCUUCAACUUCAAAACAGUCCGUCAAGCCAAGAAUAUCAUGGAACUAAUGAUACAAGAAAAAUCCUUUGGUAAAUGCCACUCUCCCUGCAUUUAUUAUGGUAACUCCCUGCUCCUGAAUUCUGCCAUGCAGCCAGAUCUGACAGUGAGCCGGACAUACAGCGGACCCAUCUGUCUGCAGGACCCUCUGGACAAGGAGCUCAUGACAGAGUCCUCACUCUUUAACCCUUUGUCGGACAUCAAAGUGAAAGUCCAGAGCUCGUUCAUGGUUUCCCUGGGAGUGUCUGAGAGAGCUGAGUACCACGGCAAGAAUCAUUCCAGGACUUUUCCCCAUGGAAACAACCACAGCUUUAGUACAAUGCAUCCCAGAAAUAAAAUGCCCUACAUCCAAAAUCUGUCAUCACUCCCCACAAGGACAGAACUGAGGACAACUGGUGUCUUUGGCCAUUUAGGGGGGCGCUUAGUAAUGCCAAAUACAGGGGUGAGCUUACUCAUACCACACGGUGCCAUCCCAGAGGAGAAUUCUUGGGAGAUUUAUAUGUCCAUCAACCAAGGUGAACCCAGCCUCCAGUCAGAUGGCUCUGAGGUGCUCCUGAGUCCUGAAGUCACCUGUGGUCCUCCAGACAUGAUCGUCACCACUCCCUUUGCAUUGACCAUCCCGCACUGUGCAGAUGUCAGUUCUGAGCAUUGGAAUAUCCAUUUAAAGAAGAGGACACAGCAGGGCAAAUGGGAGGAAGUGAUGUCAGUGGAAGAUGAAUCUACAUCCUGUUACUGCCUUUUGGACCCCUUUGCGUGUCAUGUGCUCCUGGACAGCUUUGGGACCUAUGCGCUCACUGGAGAGCCAAUCACAGACUGUGCCGUGAAGCAACUGAAGGUGGCGGUUUUUGGCUGCAUGUCCUGUAACUCCCUGGAUUACAACUUGAGAGUUUACUGUGUGGACAAUACCCCUUGUGCAUUUCAGGAAGUGGUUUCAGAUGAAAGGCAUCAAGGUGGACAGCUCCUGGAAGAACCAAAAUUGCUGCAUUUCAAAGGGAAUACCUUUAGUCUUCAGAUUUCUGUCCUUGAUAUUCCCCCAUUCCUCUGGAGAAUUAAACCAUUCACUGCCUGCCAGGAAGUCCCGUUCUCCCGCGUGUGGUGCAGUAACCGGCAGCCCCUGCACUGUGCCUUCUCCCUGGAGCGUUAUACGCCCACUACCACCCAGCUGUCCUGCAAAAUCUGCAUUCGGCAGCUCAAAGGCCAUGAACAGAUCCUCCAAGUGCAGACAUCAAUCCUAGAGAGUGAACGAGAAACCAUCACUUUCUUCGCACAAGAGGACAGCACUUUCCCUGCACAGACUGGCCCCAAAGCCUUCAAAAUUCCCUACUCCAUCAGACAGCGGAUUUGUGCUACAUUUGAUACCCCCAAUGCCAAAGGCAAGGACUGGCAGAUGUUAGCACAGAAAAACAGCAUCAACAGGAAUUUAUCUUAUUUCGCUACACAAAGUAGCCCAUCUGCUGUCAUUUUGAACCUGUGGGAAGCUCGUCAUCAGCAUGAUGGUGAUCUUGACUCCCUGGCCUGUGCCCUUGAAGAGAUUGGGAGGACACACACGAAACUCUCAAACAUUUCAGAAUCCCAGCUUGAUGAAGCCGACUUCAACUACAGCAGGCAAAAUGGACUCUAGUCCACUUCCUCCCAUGAGACAGAGUGAUGGCCAGCUUGGGGACAUUUGCUUUAAAUGGGAAAGAGGCCGCUUUCUGCCCAGUGGCGUUGGGGGAAUUCAGCCUUCAUUUAUAAUCAGUGAGAUUCCCCUGUUGAAGAAACUAAAUUUUAUAUAGGUAAAACAUGUUAAUAGGGAAGAGUACAAGCUCUCUUACAUAUAAGAGGGCUCUACUAUCUCCUUGGAAUCCACAUUUGGGUUAACUCCUCAGAUUUGGAGUGGCAAGGAUAAAAGUGAGGGCAGAAGUAGCUGUGGGAAAAGAUGAGCUAUGAUAAUGCUGGGAAGGCAGAGAUUGAUUAAGUGCAUGCUUUGAAAUAGGUUUUUAAUGAUGUGCCCCAAAGGGCCAGCUGAUUCUGGUACUAGAUUGUCAGAGUUUUCUACCAACUGGCAUCUGUGAUGUCAGAGAUCAUUGUAAAAAUGGCUUUUAGACGUGAAACAGGGUUGCCAACCCAUUUGUAUGACUUCAACAACGUCAAGGAGGGCAUUUAGAAUUUAGAAUCUGAGCACAUCACACCAGCACCAGCUCCCUGUCUCUUCUAGCCACUUAAUGGAGACACAAUGGAGAGGUAAGACAGACCACAAACUAGUUCUUAUAGUGUACUCCACCUUUUACUUUUUUCCUGAGACAAAUCUACCCUUAUUCUUUCUUCCUCUUCCUUACCCCUUGCAGUAGGGAGGUAUCAAGGAGCAUAAUUAAACUUGUCAAUACGGAAAGUUGUUUUUUCUAACACAACAAAGUGGGACCAUCUCUAUUCCCAUCUAAGCCACUCAAAUUGCUGAGUGCUAUUAGAACACAGCUUAUUACAUGGAUAUGGGGACAGGAGAGAUUAAAGCAGGUUCAAAAACACAUGAACUGCAGAUGCCAUAGGCCUCAAAUCAGCUGUAAUUCUAGGAGACACGUGUUGAUCUAGUUAUCUAACAUUGUUGUUAUAAGAAAAUGAGUUUACUGCAUUUUUCAAUCCAGAUUCUUGAAAUUGUCUAACAUGUGGGUACUGUGUCAUCACAAAAUCUCUCAGUAAGGCUAUAUGUGAUCCUCAUUUUGCCUCUUGGGAAAUUAGCAGAUAGUCUUUGCUCUAAAUGAUAUCUGAGUAAAUAGACUUGAGGAAUCCUCUACCACAGUGUCCCUGAAACCACAUGCAUCAUUCAGGAAGCCUUCACCCUGUGACUAUUCAGCCUCCCUGAAUAUGCUUUCUCUAUAGAACCACUAACAUAUGGCUAUUGCUCUAUGAUUUUUUUUUUUACAUUAGGAGGCAGUGAUAUUGUGGAAGAUUGAAAUCCACAGAUAAUUCAUGACCCUCAUCUUAUCACUUUACUCCAUCUUUUUAUCCUAUUAAAUUAUUUUUGACAAGAUGUCCUGGUAGACUAAAGGUGAACAGAUUUGCUCUUGCUCAUCUUCUGGUGGAUAUUUUAACUUGCUAUUCACAAUCAGGACAACCAAAGUCAAGGACCCAGAUGAACCACAAGGCAGCUAGUCAGCUACUUAGAGGUUGGUUACAUUCGAAUAAAAAGUAGUCAGGGAAUGGGGGAGGUGGGGAGUUGGGGAGUACUUGGCAGUUGGGAUAUGAUCCAUUUUUUUAAACAAGUUUUUUGUAGAUCCCUUGUAAAAUAAUAAUAAUAAUGUUGUGAAUCUCCAUGCCAAGUGAAAAAGGCCUAAAGAUGAGUUGAAUUUGUGAUACCAUGGGUAAGGCAUGGAAGAACUCUUGAAUGUGUUGGCCAUUUUCUCUAACUAACAUGUGGUAUGUAUGGUCCCCUAUAUUAGAUAGAAGUCUUUGCUACAUGUAAUUCAAAAGCAUCUCGCUUUUCUCAGGAACCAAAGGCUUAUGAUGUAGGACAAAGAAAUCAUCUUAGAACUGUCAAGCAUAUUUUCACAAUACCAUGUCAAGAUCAGGAAAACACCCUUUUGCUAGUGUGCUUAACUUAUUUAUUUCUUCUAGGAAACAAUAGAUAAACAGCAUGAAAAUGUAAAUCAUCUGGCAUCACUGAUAGAAUUUCUGAAAGAGAAAGAGAAGUAGAUGGUCAACCAGUCACUAGUUGGUUGGCAUGAGGUGGUGUGCAGAGGAAAGCUGCAUUCACUAUUGAGUAAAAACUUGUAGAAAGCACAUUAUAGAGCUUAUGUUGGAAUCCAUCUUGGAGGAUUUUUGUUUUAAACUGUCUUUAGCAUUUUCCCUCUUCCCUUCUAAUGGGCAUUAUAAUUGUUUCAUCUACUCUGUGAAUCUACAUAGGUCUUUUUUUUUAGAUGUUUGAUACAUUUUAAGUAUUUUUAAAUAGAUGAAAAUUCUAAAUGAUUUUCCCUCAAAUCUAUCUAGAUUAUUUUAAGAUGAGACAAGAUUAUUGUCAAUCCCUGAAUGUCUGGAGUUACCUCCCAUGGAUUUUUUUUUCCUUUGGCCUGGGUUUUAUAAACAACUUGAACAUCAUAUCAUAUAGGAUAACAAAGGAGGAAGUUAACUUAAUUCACCUCAGACUUCAGCCUAAGAUUCAAUCAAAUUCAUCCUUCAGCCUGUCUUGUUUCUUCUUUAUGUUUCUUUUACUUAUUGCUGCUAGGAUCCUACAUAGGAUUUCUAUAGAAAUGUAUGAAAUUCUGUGGUCACUGCAUGUCAGGAUUGCACAGUAUGUUACAAUACAAUUUCAAAGAGAACCCACAUUUGUGAGAUUUACAGACCAAGGUGUGGUGGAGGAGGUAGAAUUGCAGAUCAGAUAAAAAGUGAGCUUACACUUGAACUUAGUUAUUCACUGUGACCUAAAUUUAGUCCUAUUGUAAUAUGUGCCUGUCACAACACAAAUACCCCUCUUGAAAGAGAUUUACUCAUCUAUCCAAGCACUUAAUUUGGAAAUUUUAUUGUCCUAUUGCAAAAUGAAACAAAAUUAAAAGUGGCCUCGAGUACUUGGUAAGUUACUUAAAAUUUUUACAAAAAUAUCCCACUCAAUGCCAAAUCUUUCAGUCCUCAAAGGCAUUUAAGUCCAAUAGUCAUGCUUUAAAUAUGGCUUUAAAUUAUGCCACCAAAAUGGUGCACUUCACAGAUUCACCAGACUGUAGCAUCAUAAAGUUAAUUUACAGUUUUUACAACAUUGCUUCUACAUUCUUACUGGUUUACAUUAAAAUCCUUUAAGCCAAAAGGAAGCUUGCUCUAUGGAUUUAAAUGCAAACUUCAUUUACCAGUGCAGGAAGUCUCAUAAAACUCAGAUGUACUCCCACAAAAAUUUUAUUGGCCUUUUUGUAAGAGAUGAAAAAGAAUUGACACAGUUCUCUUUAAAGAGAAGAACUUUUUUAUUAUUAUUUUUAUCUCCAACUGCAGGUGGUGUCUUUUGCCAAGGUCUCUGUAUUUUUCUUUCAGUUGUCUUUGGGAGGGGAUGUUAAGUCAAAUCACUAAAACAGGGUUCUCUUUGGAUUAAAAGUUCUGGAUUUAUUGCAACUAUUUUCCUUGAGAAACAUUCUCAGCAUCAGGAUUGAUAAACAAAUGUAGAUGAUUAAAAUAGGAUAAUUGGUUUUAGAUAAUAUCUUCUACUGCCAAACUUCUGGCAAAUUUACCUGUGAAUUUCAAAAUGUUAUAAAAUCUCUUGAUAUGCUUUUGUUUUUCCUUUUAGCCAUUUUCUCUUCAAUUUCUUAGUCCCUCUGCCCUCUGUAAAUGUGUUGAGUGAUAUAGCUAUCAGAUGUAUUGAAGGCAAAGUUCUCGCAGAGGUCUCUGUUCCAGCUCUGUAAAGGUCACAGGAAUCGUGAAGGAGCUGAGAAAUCUUCCUCUCCGGCCCACUGUCUGUGGCCCAUUGUCAUUGUUUCCUCAUGAAACAUUGCAGAGUUUGAAUCCUCAGUAACUCUCAUUGACUGGAUUAGAGGUGAUGGCCACAGCAAAUGGGAGAGCAAAAUGUUGGCCUACAGAGAAUGACACAAUUUUAUUCGCCUUUGGUGUUAGUUGCCAUAGUGCUGUAUUUGAAAAUCGAUGCUUUAGCCAAAAGCUGAAUGACCACCGUUUCCGUAGUUUCCACUGUUUUGUCUGCAUAGAAUUUUCCUGAACUACAAGCAAAAAUGUAUUUUGUCCAAUGUCACAAAAGUGAAAAUGUUACUAAUCUUAGAUGUGUUGCAUAUUUUGUGUUUUUACGUUCCAAACUCUUUCAAAAGCUGCCGUUACAAAGCUGUUUGGCUGUAUUGACAGCAUGUGGUGUUUUUACAAAAGCAAUUCUAGGAGAGCCAGUGUCUACCAUGAACUCCUGACAUCCCCACUCCAGGGUCAUUCAUGACAUUGAAAUGGCAACUUGUACACUGUAAUUCUUCGAAAAGUAACAGGGGAUGGAAAUCAGACCUGGCCGUUAGUCACUAGUGUGUAGUACCGUGAUCUGAAGUAGGAAAUUUAACUGACAUAGAAUAAUUGUGGUUUUUGAAGCAGCUACUCAUUGCUUUUUCCUUUUGCUGUGAAGAUCAUGGAUUGGGAAUGUCCUCGUGAGGUGGACCUAAGGCAGUAACAUUUAAACUUCAUGUCCUAGCACCCGCCCUCCAUCUGACCCAAAGAUAAAAAAGGCAUCAAGCUUCAUGGUUAUGCCUAAGCUUAAAAAUUCCCUUCCCCACUACUAAUAUUGAGUUCAGCAGGGCCCCAUCUUACUUAUUUUUCAAAAAAGUUAUAGCUUUGAAUUAUAGACUAUAUUACUAAAUUUGGUAAGGUAGUUCUUUGCAUGAAUGGGAAUGUGUGUCAAAAUACUUUCACAAAAGGCAUGAUUACAAUGGAAAUGCCCCUUUGCCUCCAGUUUUGCUAACCCUAAAAAGUAUUUCACUAAUUUCAAGCACUGUUUACACUCAAAUCCCAAAAUUGGCCAAAUUAUAUAAUUCUCUUAAAUUUUCAUUUCUGUAGGUGGAGAUUUAACUAUGGUUCUGGUGAAUCAUAGAAGGGAGAGACAAUAUUUGAGGGGAGUUUAUCAGCAGAAUAUCAUGCCUUAUGACCCCAUUACUGAAACACAGACAUUACAAUCAGAAAUAGACCUAAUAAUUCCAAUAUCCCUCCAUUAACUAGUUCCAGUGAUGCUGAGAGACACAGCACCCUGUGCCAGGUAUCAGAAAUAUAAGCCUCAGCAGAGGGUAACUGAAAACUUUCAAUCAGAAACACUCUCCAAGGCUUAUGGCUAGAUUAUGUAGGUCACUACCAUUCAAAACUUUUCUAUACAAAGGUGGAAAAGCACUCAGAAUCUGGGAAUUUUCUGGUUGGAAGAACAAUGUUCUCCUUUUCCAAAUUGGAAUAAAGACUCAGAAUUACCCAUUCUUCAUAAUCAUGUCUGAUUGGUACAUACACUCCAGGAAGUCUCAACCUAGAAACAUUUCCAACCUAAGCAUUUAAAGGAAAACUGGCUCAUUCUUCUGACCCAAACUCAAAAAAUAUGAGUACUUGCGUACCUCCAUUUCUGCAUGAAGAUUUUAAAACAGAUUUCAUUUUUUUCUGUUUAUUUUGGGAAGGUGCGUGGGGGUGUUCUUUCAAGUGAUUCACAUCUCAAACCCAUACCACUCUCAACUUUUAUUUGAUGUGUUCAAAGCCAAAAAAUAAAAUAAAAUAAAGCAGGGCUGAACACUUAAUUUGACAUGAAGCUGAAGGACUGAGCAAGCCAGAGGAGAGAGGUUGAAUGAAGCAUAGCCUUGGCUUCAUACCACACUUUUUGUGCCUUGUAUUAUCAAUGUAAAUUCUGAAUGUUGUACAGUAAACUUGGAUGGACUUCUUAGAAAAGGCUGCACUGGCUUCUUUUUCAGCACAUGUACAUAUCUAUAAAUAUAUAUACAUAUAUAUUUGGUAAUGCCAAACAGCUCUGUUAUAUUGUAUUGAACAAAAUGGACGGUUUGGAUGUUUUAUGUCGAGUUUGCAAAAAAAAAAAAAAAAAAAAAAACUGGAUGGUUGCAGACUUUUCAAGAUAAAUGUACAGACGUAAAUUACUGCAUAUCAGUUAUUUAUGAAUAAAGAGUCUUUUAUUGACA